GCUCGGCUUGUGGGACGCCCGCGGUCGGAUGCCCUCCGUCCGCUCCCUCCUCCGCCUCUUGGCCGCCGCGGCGGCCUGUGGCGCCUUCGCCUUCCUGGGCUAUUGUAUUUACCUCAACCGGAAGCGGCGCGGGGACCCCGCGUUCAAGCGCCGCCUGCGGGACAAAAGAAGAGCAGAGCCUCAAAAGGCUGAGGAGCAGGGCACGCAGGUGCAGUGCUUUCGAUCCGCACAGUUGUGGGAUCCAACGAAGAAUAAAAAGUUGCAAGAACUUUUCUUGCAAGAGGUACGGAUGGGAGAACUUUGGUUAUCUAGAGGAGAGCACAGAAUGGGGAUUCAACACCUCGGCAAUGCCCUUUUAGUGUGCGAGCAACCACGGGAACUUCUGAAAGUUUUCAAACACACUCUCCCUCCCAAGGUAUUUGAGAUGCUGUUGCACAAAAUUCCCCUUAUUUGCCAGCAAUUUGAGGCAGACAUGAAUGAACAGGACUGCUUGGAGGAUGAUCCUGAUUGAAAAACAUUUCAACGUAUCCACAGUCCAGUGAGAAUACUAUGGUACCAUACAGUAUAAACAACUGCUCAGUGAUAUUUCCAUUUAUUUUACUUUGAGUAAUAAAAAUUUUUCUAUCUCAUA